CUCCCCUUCCUCGCCGGCGUCCGCGUCCCCGCGCCGAGCUGCUCGGGCUCCCUGAGCCCCAGAUCUGACCCCUUCCCUUCGGCAACCUGAACGACUCCCGCCUUCCACGGAAGGGACCGAGCCCGUGCCAAACAGGCUGAGCGAUUUGGGAGUGAGGAGCCAUCCUACCGCUUUCCCCAACCUGGAAACAGCAAAGCGCAAGGCCUCUGAGUCAGUUAGGUCUCUGCCACCCACGGGCAAAGGAUGCUCUCCUCCAUCCUCCUUCCUCCCUCCACCGAAAUCGGAGAGCCGCGGGCCUGAUCCAAAGAGGCAUCCCCUUCUCGUUCAUUCCCCAGAGGCCUCAAUACAAACCCCAGGAGUUGGCCCCUCUCCUUUUGCUACAAAUCCUUGCCUUGCAAAGGGGAGAGGUGGUUUGUGCUCCCCCUACUGCCUAUAUCGACUUCGCCCGGCAGAAGCUAGAUCCCAAGAUUGCUGUGGCUGCGCAGAACUGCUACAAAGUGACUAAUGGGGCUUUUACUGGGGAGAUCAGCCCUGGCAUGAUCAAAGACUGCGGAGCCACGUGGGUGGUCCUGGGGCACUCAGAGAGAAGGCAUGUCUUUGGGGAGUCAGAUGAGCUGAUUGGGCAGAAAGUGGCCCAUGCUCUGGCAGAGGGACUCGGAGUAAUCGCCUGCAUUGGGGAGAAGCUAGAUGAAAGGGAAGCUGGCAUCACUGAGAAGGUUGUUUUCGAGCAGACAAAGGUCAUCGCAGAUAACGUGAAGGACUGGAGCAAGGUCGUCCUGGCCUAUGAGCCUGUGUGGGCCAUUGGUACUGGCAAGACUGCAACACCCCAACAGGCCCAGGAAGUACACGAGAAGCUCCGAGGAUGGCUGAAGUCCAACGUCUCUGAUGCGGUGGCUCAGAGCACCCGUAUCAUUUAUGGAGGCUCUGUGACUGGGGCAACCUGCAAGGAGCUGGCCAGCCAGCCUGAUGUGGAUGGCUUCCUUGUGGGUGGUGCUUCCCUCAAGCCCGAAUUCGUGGACAUCAUCAAUGCCAAACAAUGAGCCCCAUCCAUCUUCCCUACCCUUCCUGCCAAGCCAGGGACUAAGCAGCCCAGAAGCCCAGUAACUGCCCUUUCCCUGCAUAUGCUUCUGAUGGUGUCAUCUGCUCCUUCCUGUGGCCUCAUCCAAACUGUAUCUUCCUUUACUGUUUAUAUCUUCACCCUGUAAUGGUUGGGACCAGGCCAAUCCCUUCUCCACUUACUAUAAUGGUUGGAACUAAACGUCACCAAGGUGGCUUCUCCUUGGCUGAGAGAUGGAAGGCGUGGUGGGAUUUGCUCCUGGGUUCCCUAGGCCCUAGUGAGGGCAGAAGAGAAACCAUCCUCUCCCUUCUUACACCGUGAGGCCAAGAUCCCCUCAGAAGGCAGGAGUGCUGCCCUCUCCCAUGGUGCCCGUGCCUCUGUGCUGUGUAUGUGAACCACCCAUGUGAGGGAAUAAACCUGGCACUAGGUCUUGUGGUUUGUCUGCCUUCACUGGACUUGCCCAGAUAAUCUUCCUUUUUGAGGCAGCUAUAUAAAUGAUCAUUUGUGCAAGAAAAAAAAAAAAACAAGAACAGGUUUCUAUAACAACA